AGUGUCGUGCUCUCCUCGGUAGGGGAGGAAUUGGUUAGGCGGCGGCGGCGGCGAAGCGGCGGCGGCGGCUGUAGGGGAGCAGCGGCAGUGGCGGCGACGGCGAGGAGGUGUUCGGUUUGCGCAGCGUAGAAACGCCCGCAGCUUCAGAGAAGGAGUUCUUGUGGGACCAAAUUAGGCAUUCUGAACCCACGCCGGCUUAGCUGGGCCGAGUCCAGGCGCUGCCGCACGUACAGUUUUGGUGGCGGUGACAGACACUGUUCUUGACUCUAGGGGCCUAUUAGGCCGACGUCUGAGGCGCAGAUCGCUGGCUCUCGACGCAUUACUCUUUACGCCUUACAUUUCUGUCUUCCUUCCUGGGUCAGUGAUUCCCGGACCCUGGAAGAGAAGAGGGUGGCUAAUGAUUAAGAUUCUUGGUAACAGCUGGCCCAGGUUUCUACAGAUGCUUGGGAUGGAAGAAGUUUGAGUGACCUAUCCUGUGUUUAUCCUCCUUGCCGUAGCUGAGUUGAUCUUUUUGAAACCCUCUUCCCAGACUCUUGGAUUUAUUUAUUUUAUUCCAGUGUGAAUGCAUGUUUUUUCCCUCAUAGAUGGCAGUUCUGGAUUAGCAGUUUUAAGCAUGAGCAGUAAUAUCCAGACCAACAUGGAAUGGAGGAUGUCCCUUAAUCUCCUCACAUGGCUAUCCCUUGUGCAGUCCUCUUUUAACAAGCUUUCCUUAAAGUUUCCCAUGUCUCAAUGGACUCCUGAAUAUAACGAGCUCUACACCUUAAAAGUGGAUAUGAAGAGUGAGAUUCCUUCUGAUGCACCAAAGACACAGGAGAGUCUGAAAGGGAUCCUUUUGCAUCCAGAGCCCAUUGGGGCAGCCAAAAGUUUUCCUGCAGGAGUUGAGAUGAUUAAUAGUAAAGUGGGGAAUGAAUUCUCUCACCUGUGUGAUGAUUCUCAAAAGCAAGAGAAGGAAAUGAAUGGUAACCAGCAAGAACAAGAAAAAAGUCUCGUUGUGAGGAAAAAACGCAAAAGCCAGCAGGCUGGCCCUUCGUAUGUGCAGAAUUGUGUUAAAGAAAACCAGGGAAUAUUAGGACUGAGGCAACACCUAGGGACACCAAGUGAUGAAGAUAAUGAUUCCUCUUUUAGUGAUUGUCUUUCUUCUCCUUCAUCUAGUCUGCAUUUUGGAGAUUCUGAUACUGUGACUUCAGAUGAGGAUAAAGAAGUCUCUGUAAGACAUUCCCAGACCAUUUUGAAUGCUAAAAGUAGAAGCCAUAGUGCACGGUCUCAUAAGUGGCCUCGGACUGAGACAGAAUCUGUAUCGGGAUUGUUAAUGAAAAGACCCUGUUUACAUGGCAGUUCGUUACGGAGACUUCCAUGCAGAAAGAGAUUUGUAAAAAAUAAUUCCUCACAGAGGACACAGAAACAAAAAGAGAGGAUAUUAAUGCAGAGGAAGAAACGAGAAGUGUUAGCUCGAAGAAAAUAUGCCUUGCUACCUAGUUCUAGUAGUUCCAGUGAGAAUGACCUCAGCAGUGAAUCCUCUUCUAGCUCAUCAACUGAAGGAGAAGAAGAUUUGUUUGUUUCUGCCAGUGAAAACCACCAAAACAAUCCAGCUGUUCCCUCAGGAAGUAUUGAUGAAGAUGUUGUGGUGAUAGAAGCUUCCUCCACUCCCCAGGUUACUGCCAAUGAAGAAAUUAAUGUUACCUCAACUGACAGUGAAGUGGAGAUUGUAACAGUUGGAGAAAGCUAUCGGUCUCGUUCAACCCUUGGACACUCCAGAUCUCAUUGGAGCCAGGGUUCCAGUUCUCAUGCAAGUCGGCCACAGGAGCCACGGAACCGCAGUAGGAUUUCUACUGUUAUACAGCCCUUGAGGCAGAAUGCAGCAGAAGUUGUGGACCUUACCGUUGAUGAAGAUGAACCUACUGUAGUACCAACCACUUCUGCAAGAAUGGAAUCACAAGCUACUAGCGCUUCCAUUAACAAUUCAAAUCCAUCUACCUCUGAGCAGGCCUCUGAUACUGCUUCAGCUGUCACCAGUAGCCAACCUUCCACAGUGUCAGAGACUUCAGCUACUCUUACAAGCAAUAGUACCACUGGCACUUCUAUAGGAGAUGACUCAAGGAGAACUACAUCUAGUGCUGUAACGGAAACUGGCCCUCCUGCAAUGCCAAGGUUACCUUCCUGCUGUCCCCAGCACUCACCAUGUGGAGGGUCGUCACAGAACCACCAUGCAUUAGGACAUCCUCAUACAAGUUGCUUUCAGCAGCAUGGUCACCAUUUUCAACAUCAUCACCACCACCACCAUACUCCCCACCCAGCUGUCCCAGUUUCUCCUUCCUUUAGUGAUCCUGCUUGCCCUGUGGAAAGACCUCCACAAGUACAAGCACCUUGUGGAGCAAAUAGUAGUUCUGGUACCAGCUAUCAUGAACAGCAGGCAUUGCCAGUGGACCUGAGCAACAGUGGUAUCAGAAGUCAUGGAAGUGGCAGUUUUCAUGGAGCAUCUGCAUUUGACCCCUGCUGCCCUGUUUCUUCCUCCCGAGCUGCAAUCUUUGGCCAUCAGGCCGCUGCUGCUGCCCCAAGUCAACCUUUAUCAUCAAUAGAUGGCUAUGGAUCAAGCAUGGUUGCGCAGCCCCAGCCCCAGCCCCCUCCACAGCCCUCUCUCUCAUCAUGUCGACAUUACAUGCCACCCCCUUAUGCCUCUUUGACAAGGCCACUUCAUCAUCAAGCUUCUGCCUGCCCGCAUUCUCAUGGAAACCCCCCUCCUCAGACUCAGCCUCCGCCUCAAGUGGAUUAUGUUAUUCCUCAUCCUGUACAUGCUUUCCAUUCUCAAAUAUCUUCUCAUGCAACAUCUCAUCCUGUGGCACCCCCACCACCAACUCACUUAGCCAGUACAGCUGCACCAAUCCCUCAGCAUCUUCCUCCUACACACCAGCCAAUUUCGCACCAUAUUCCAGCCACAGCACCUCCAGCACAGAGACUGCAUCCUCAUGAAGUGAUGCAGAGGAUGGAAGUUCAAAGGAGGAGGAUGAUGCAGCAUCCAACUGGUCUUUUUGUGUUCUGUGUUUCCAGGCGGGCACAUGAACGCCCCCCACCCCAUCCACAUAGGAUGCACCCAAACUAUGGUCAUGGGCAUCAUAUUCAUGUGCCUCAGACUAUGUCCUCACAUCCUCGACAGGCUCCAGAGAGGUCUGCCUGGGAACUGGGAAUUGAAGCUGGAGUGACUGCAGCUACUUAUACACCUGGUGCAUUGCAUCCUCACUUGGCCCAUUAUCACGCACCUCCUCGACUUCAUCACUUACAAUUAGGAGCUCUUCCUUUAAUGGUUCCUGAUAUGGCAGGCUAUCCUCACAUCCGUUACAUUUCAUCAGGAUUGGAUGGAACAUCAUUCAGAGGUCCUUUCAGGGGCAAUUUUGAGGAACUGAUUCAUUUGGAAGAAAGAUUAGGCAAUGUCAAUCGUGGAGCAUCCCAGGGGACAAUUGAAAGAUGUACAUAUCCACAUAAAUACAAAAAGGUAACAACUGAUUGGUUCUCACAGAGGAAACUGCACUGCAAACAAGAUGGGGAAGAAGGGACUGAGGAAGACACAGAGGAAAAAUGUACUAUCUGUUUGUCUAUUUUAGAGGAAGGUGAAGAUGUGAGACGUCUUCCAUGUAUGCACCUUUUCCACCAAGUGUGUGUUGACCAAUGGUUGAUUACCAAUAAGAAGUGCCCCAUAUGCAGAGUGGACAUUGAGGCCCAGCUGCCAAGUGAAAGUUGACACCAUGUUUCAGAACUCUUGCCCUCCCUCUCAUUCCCAUCCUUCCUGGUACUGCAGUCAACCAAAGAUGGCAUGACUUACCUGCGCAGAUUUGGAAGCAUUGAACUUAGAGUGCUGGCUCUGCUAUAUGGUACAACUAAUGCUAGACCUACAGUUUAUGUAUACAGUUGAUUUUGAUGUAUUUAUAAAAGCUUUUUUUUCUAGAUUUGACAUUUUUCUGUAUCAUUUUACUGUAUUUUUGCAUGGUUCCUUGUAUUGCAUUUCUUUGCACAUAUUAUGGGCUUGUGACCCUAAACUUGCAGGCAAGGUUAGCUGCUUUAGUAAGUAGAAUUUUGUGGUCUUUUUGUUUUUUACAUAGUACCAAGCCUUGAUAAUUAUGAAUUUUUUAUCCAUUACUAACCUUUAAUUUAAUCAAUCAUGUACUUUAGUUUAAUGUAUAAAGAUCCUCUAGAAAAUGAUAAUAUUGUGUAUUAAGACAUUCCUUAAUUAGGACAAAAUGGCUGCUGUAUAUUUACUAUAUGGAGUUCUGAGUUAAAUACCAUCCUUAAUACUGGGAACAGAAUACAACCCAUAUAAAUCAGAUGCAGGUGGUAGUCACAUCACCAGAGUGAUCAGUAUAAAUUUUCUUGGUGUAUCCUUUUCCUUUCAACACAGUGCAGAUAAGAGUUGAAUAUUGAUAUCAUACAUUUAGACUGCUGUUCUGAUUGCAUUUAUCUUUUUCCUACAUCAUUUAGAAUUUUAUUUCCCUGAUUCAGUUUUUGCUGCUGUGAAACAGCUCUGAUGAACACUAAAUAUUAAUUUCAAUUAGCUAGAUUGUACAUACUUGCAGAUUUAACAAAAUUUUAGGGAAAUUGAAAAAGACAUGUAGAAUUUGUUGUCUUCUGCUAAGCACGAAAAGUUAAGAUAUCUGCUUACAUUGAUUUUGUAGACACAUUAAGUCAAGAUUUGGAAUUUAAGUCACUGGCAGGUAUCUGUGCAUUCAUAGAACUUAUAAAGGUCCCAGGAUCACUUUUAAGGGAUUUUUAUUAGUUUAAAGGUAAAUAAAGUCAGCUGAAUCUACAUGUCUCUUGUUUUAUUUCUCUCUAAACUUGAAAACAGUAAAUCUGCAGAUACUGUGAGGCACAAAUUAUACUGUCAACCUACUGUUGCUAUGGUUAUAUACUCCCACUUCAUACAUUACCAAGAGUCGAUCACUGAUUUAAAAUUUUUAAUUUCUAUAGUUAAGAUUUACUGCAUAAUAUAGAAUAUAAAGUUAAGUUAACAUACUAACAUUUCUCCUUUGGAGGAAGUUUUAAUCUACUUCAGGAUGCAUAUUAUUAUCAAGAUACUUUCAUAUACAGGAUAGCCUAAUUUUAUUUGUUUAAAUAUGCUUAAUAUGCCCCAGAUUGCAAAUGCAUCCAGUCAGUAAUAUCACUGUCUGUAUGUGGAGGACAUGUUCCCAUGGAUCAUAUGUGAAGAUGUCAAUAAGCUUGCAUUAAGCCACCUGCUUUGUAAGUGGAUUGAUUAAUAAAUAACUUAUAUUUCUAUUGUCUUUGUGUUUCAUAAUUAGUUUUUAUAAAAACAGUUUACAUUAAACAUCUUGGAAUUCAACAAUAGUGAUCUCACUCAAAUUGACAUUUGCAUAAUUUGACAUUUAUAUUCAUUCAGUUAUGACUACUUGCCCUUUUCUUCAUAUUAGUAAAUGUUACACUGUAGUAGUUGUCAAUGUUAACAGGCUUCAACAUAGUAUGUGUGCAGAUGGACGAUGGAUUUAAAGAGCAUACCUUAUGAUUAAACCGAGGUUAUAGAAGGUCAGGGGAGAGUGAAGGAGUCAGUGACCUAUGUCUGCCAUCUUACUGGGGAAAAGAGCAAGUAGCCUGUCUUCCUUUAAGUAAGUAGCCUGUAAUGGAUGUACUACUUUGCCACUGGAAUACCCCGGGUCUGUGCCAAGGGACUGAAGAAGUGUAAGAUGGGGAGAACUGUAUGUCAUGGAGUCCUCUUGACGUUCCCCCAGAUACAAGUAAAGCACAGGUGGAUUUCUCUAUUUUUGAAUACUACAUCAGAUUUAGAUGCACGACUACCUGUUGACUUGUUUUAUAAUUGCUACUGAUUUUUUUAAUGUAGGCAAAGCUUUGUUACUUUGAAAUUUAUUUAAUAAAAGUAUUUGUGACAUAAACCUGAAUUGUUAAUAUAGGAGCUUAUUAAGCUACUGCCAUUAGUUAUCGAAAAAUGUGAUAAGUAAUGAAGAAAGUAAGGAAGAAAAUGACUUUGAACAUUUUGACUUUUUGUGCUUUGUUUUGGUGUCUUCCAUAUCCUGCUGCAUCUUAUAUGUCAAAAUGAACAUUUCAGUGGUAGCUGUCCAAAUACAUAAAAACUAAAAUUCUUUUGUUAGCAAGUCCUUAUUUUUAUUGUUGUUAACAUGCAAGUGAUAAACUGAUAAUUUGAAACAUUUUUCUUACUCUGGUGACUUUCUUUUAGCUGCUAGCACACUUCAGCAUUUGAACCAUAACAGUUGUGAUAAACUGAUCGUUUGAAACGUU